GUAUUGAGCGAGGCACCGGGACGUCGGCGGCUGGCGGAGCCGGGCGGGCGAAGCUGGAGCGGCGGUGGCGGCGGCGUAGGGAGGCCGGGGCCGGGGCUGAGGCCGCGGCCGGGUCUGCGAGGCCCUUGGGGCGGCAGGCGGCGGCGGCCCGGGGCUCGAGCCCGGAGGCAGGAGCAGCCGCCAUGGCCGAGAGCAUCAUAAUUCGUGUCCAGUCCCCGGAUGGAGUGAAGCGGAUCACAGCAACAAAGAGAGAAACAGCAGCAACAUUUUUGAAAAAGGUUGCAAAGGAGUUUGGCUUCCAAAAUAAUGGCUUCUCGGUUUACAUCAAUAGAAACAAGACCGGAGAGAUAACAGCCUCCUCCAACAAAUCCCUCAACUUGCUAAAAAUCAAGCAUGGCGAUUUGUUGUUCCUGUUUCCCUCGAGCCUUGCUGGGCCCUCAUCUGAAAUGGAGACGUCAGUUCCACCGGGCUUCAAAGUCUUUGGCGCUCCCAACGUGGUGGAGGAUGAGAUUGAUCAGUACCUCAGCAAACAGGACGGGAAGAUUUACAGAAGCCGAGACCCACAGCUAUGCCGCCACGGCCCUUUGGGGAAAUGCGUGCACUGCGUCCCUCUAGAGCCAUUCGAUGAGGACUAUCUAAACCAUCUCGAGCCUCCCGUGAAGCACAUGUCCUUCCACGCCUACAUCCGGAAGCUGACUGGAGGGGCUGACAAGGGGAAGUUUGUUGCCCUGGAGAACAUCAGCUGCAAGAUUAAGUCAGGGUGCGAGGGGCACCUCCCGUGGCCGAAUGGCAUCUGUACUAAGUGCCAGCCGAGCGCCAUCACGCUGAACAGACAGAAGUACAGGCAUGUGGACAAUAUCAUGUUUGAGAAUCACACCGUCGCUGACCGCUUUCUUGACUUCUGGAGAAAGACAGGGAACCAGCAUUUUGGGUACUUAUACGGACGGUACACGGAGCACAAAGACAUUCCCCUUGGCAUCAGGGCUGAAGUGGCUGCGAUUUAUGAGCCACCUCAGAUUGGUACACAGAACAGCUUGGAGCUUCUUGAGGAUCCAAAAGCUGAAGUGGUCGAUGAAAUUGCUGCCAAACUUGGCCUGCGGAAGGUUGGCUGGAUAUUUACAGACCUCGUCUCAGAAGAUACCCGAAAGGGUACCGUCCGCUACAGUCGAAAUAAGGACACCUAUUUCCUAAGUUCAGAAGAGUGCAUCACUGCAGGAGACUUCCAGAACAAGCAUCCCAACAUGUGCCGGCUCUCUCCAGACGGACAUUUUGGAUCCAAGUUUGUUACUGCAGUGGCUACAGGUCUCUCUCUUGCAGGUGGUCCUGACAACCAAGUCCACUUUGAAGGGUACCAGGUGUCCAAUCAGUGUAUGGCACUGGUCCGUGAUGAGUGUUUGCUGCCAUGCAAGGACGCCCCGGAGCUUGGCUACGCCAAGGAGUCUAGCAGUGAGCAGUACGUGCCUGAUGUGUUUUAUAAGGACGUAGACAAGUUUGGCAACGAGAUCACCCAGCUGGCCCGGCCCCUGCCUGUGGAGUAUCUCAUCAUAGACAUCACAACAACUUUCCCCAAGGAUCCAGUUUACACUUUUUCUAUUUCGCAAAAUCCAUUUCCUAUUGAAAACCGGGAUGUAUUGGGUGAGACACAGGACUUCCAUAGCUUGGCCACCUAUUUGUCUCAGAAUACCUCAUCUGUGUUCUUGGAUACCAUCUCAGAUUUCCACCUCUUGCUGUUCCUGGUCACCAAUGAAGUUAUGCCUCUGCAGGACAGCAUCAGCUUGCUGCUGGAGGCCGUGCGGACCAGAAAUGAGGAGCUCGCCCAGACAUGGAAGAGGUCUGAGCAGUGGGCCACCAUCGAGCAGCUGUGCACCUCCCGAGUAGCUGGGAUUACAGAUGUGUACCACCACACCUGGCGUUGCCAUCUUUAUGCACAGUUGGCGGGCAGCUCCCAGGUCUCCAUGAGUACGGCGCCGUCGGGGGCUCCACACACACGGCCACUGCAGCCAUGUGGGCCUGUCAGCACUGCACGUUCAUGAACCAGCCAGGCACAGGCCACUGCGAGAUGUGCAGCCUCCCCAGGACCUAGGGCGCCUGCCCUCUGCUGGCUAGGACCGGGCCCAGCCCAGCCCUUCCUGAAGCCAGAAGCGUUGCUGAGUGUGUUCCCUGUAACUGCCCCAUAGUGGGCAGCCCUGGAGGAACAAGGGGCUGGCUGUCCUGGGCUCCCUGACCCACUGAAGCUUCUCAGCACGUUCCUCCCUGGAGAGCGGGCGCCACGGCUGGUAUUCUGCAGGCUGAAUGCAGUCUCCAGACUGGAAACGCAGAGCGGCUCCUCACGCCUAAUCCUGUUGACAAGUCCCCCGCCGUGUUGGAAAGACCUCUCGCCUCUACGUGGCACCUGGAAUUGGGGCGCACAGGGAGGGGCCGAUGCUGCCACCACCCAGCCUUCUCUUUAUUUUCAGUGCUUUUUGUUUGGCCUCCCUGCCCCCAUGUUUUUCUGGCUGGGAGCUCUUGGUUACCCCCUUGUCUGACUGCUUGGUGGCAGGCACCCUGCCUGUGAGGGCCACUUUCCUCUUCUAGUAGCUGUUGUCUGGUGGGGACGCAGUGGCCCUGGACACGGCUCCCCUCUGCAGGUCUGCAGGUCGGUUUGCUGCCUGCCCUCCUCCUCUCACCCGAUGUCCAGGUGGGAUUUUAAAGUCUGCAUUGGUUAUAAUAACAGUUAUCAGUAAUUCCUGCCCAGAAGACUUUUAUUUAUUUUUUUUUAAGAUAAAAACUGCACAAAAGGGGAGUGAGAGAGACUAGUUUCCACAUCCUUCCCUCCUUUAGUGAAGCCCCCGAGGUUGUGUCCAGGGUGAUGAGUGUGGACGGGGGCACCAGUCAGUUCUCCCUUGAAGUAAACCUCAGUGCCUGAGACUUUUCUACCAAGCCACACAGCUGCAGCAACUGCAGAUACUGCGGGCUGAGCAGGAGCAGUGGUGGCGCCUGCCCUGAGGCUGCCCUGCGAUGGCCUGGGUGGGAGAGCUGGGUCACCGGUGCCGAUGCUCUGGCCCUCCCCAAUACGCUGCUUCGUCCCACUGCACCGCCUGGCUGAGGGCGUUAGGGGCUGUGCCUCUUGUGAGGGCCAUUUGGGACCUCCCUGGGGCACUGCACAAUUGAUAGUGUACCAAUAGAGGGAGACUGGGCGAUCUGGAACAGCACGUGGUGGGGUCCUGCUUGUGUGCUCUGCGUUCCUCUGUGGCGUGGCCAGGCCGGGGCAUGGCUCUUACCCGGGGAGUGGUGGGCAUCUCGAUGCUUCUUUGCCUUAAUGAUGGCCACAUCUGGGCUGCUCUGCACCCACGGGAGAGGCUGGCCCAGCUGCAGACUGCUUAGGGACUUCUGUGUCCAUCCUGGGGGGUAAGCCCACGUGACCCACAUUCUUGGCACUAUGAACAGAGAACAUUUGCCUGUUGGCUUCUGAAGUGGUCAGGGCCAUGGCUGACACCUCCAGGUCCGCCUGGCAUGGGACACCAAGUGGAAGGCCCAAGCAGCUCAUCUGCUCUUGGGACCAGGGGCCAGUUGGGUUGGGUCUGGUCACGGCAGAGCUAUUGUGGAGGGUCAGGAAGGGUGGAGAGGAGCUGGGUUGAAGCGGACUGCUGCGGAUGCAACUCCCAGCUUGCCCACCGCGGGCUGUCUGCUCUCCCUCCUAGCAGCUGUCACACUGAAGUUUUGUCCUCUGCUGUCUCCUCUGGUCCUGAGAUGAGCUGUGAGCCUAGGUGGCCAAGGCUUCCUGCAUUGCUUCCCUGUGAGUCCAAGGCCUUCCCCCACCACUGGGCAGAGGCUGGACAGCACGGACUUCUAGAGAGAGCCGCGUUGCCAGUUCCUCUCCCACUCGCUCGUCCUUAUCCACCACGCUAUUAUAGUUUCCGUUGUCCUCCACCAGCAUUUCCCUUACUCUGAAGUUCCGGCAUUCACAUCAUUCAUGUUUUCUUUUGUCUUUUAGCUAAAGGAAAAGCAUUGGCGAUUUGUCUGAUUCUGGUUUUGAGUUACUCUUUGUUCAGUAAUGCACUUUAUUUUAUUGUCCAAAGAGAGUCAGAGCUAAGCAUACAGGCUUGGGGGUGAGCCCUGCUGUGAGAGUUCAGGCCCUGGGAGGCUCAGCCACCUCCUCUUGUGGGAAGGAGGUCUCAGCCCCACCUCGCAUCUUCACCUGCCCUUGGUGUGGACACACCCUCUCAUGCUACCAGCACCAUAAUCCAGUGGGGGUGACUGGGUGCACACCUGCCCAGGUGAACACAGCGGCUGCCAGUCUCCUGGUCCCGAGAGGAGGUGGGGCCUGGCCCUGGCUCCCUCCAACCAGCUGCUCCUGGGACACAGGUGCUCCUGCUUCGGCUCUGUUUCGGCUCACAGGUGUGCAUCACUGGGCUUGGAUUUGCAUUACAUUGACCCCAGCCCUGCAGUGGAACCUAAUAAAAGCGCCUGAAGCAACU